AGCCCCGAGCGAGCGAGCGAGCGAGCGAGUUGCCGAGCGCGCCCCGUCCCUCGCGCGCGAUGCUCCCCUGGACGGCGCUCGGCCUGGCCCUGAGCUUGCGGCUGGCGCUGGCGCGGAGCGGCGCGGAGCGCGGUCCACCAGCAUCAGCCCCCCGAGGGGACCUGAUGUUCCUGCUGGACAGCUCAGCCAGCGUCUCUCACUACGAGUUCUCCCGGGUUCGGGAGUUUGUGGGGCAGCUGGUGGCUCCACUGCCCCUGGGCACCGGGGCCCUGCGUGCCAGUCUGGUGCACGUGGGCAGUCGGCCAUACACCGAGUUCCCCUUCGGCCAGCACAGCUCGGGUGAGGCUGCCCAGGAUGCGGUGCGUGCUUCUGCCCAGCGCAUGGGUGACACCCACACUGGCCUGGCGCUGGUCUAUGCCAAGGAACAGCUGUUUGCUGAAGCAUCAGGUGCCCGGCCAGGGGUGCCCAAAGUGCUGGUGUGGGUGACAGAUGGCGGCUCCAGCGACCCUGUGGGCCCCCCCAUGCAGGAGCUCAAGGACCUGGGCGUCACCGUGUUCAUUGUCAGCACCGGCCGAGGCAACUUCCUGGAGCUGUCAGCCGCUGCCUCAGCCCCUGCCGAGAAGCACCUGCACUUUGUGGACGUGGAUGACCUGCACAUCAUUGUCCAAGAGCUGAGGGGCUCCAUUCUCGACGCGAUGCGGCCGCAGCAGCUCCAUGCCACGGAGAUCACGUCCAGCGGCUUCCGCCUGGCCUGGCCACCCCUGCUGACCGCAGACUCGGGCUACUAUGUGCUGGAGCUGGUGCCCAGCGCCCAGCCGGGGGCUGCAAGACGCCAGCAGCUGCCAGGGAACGCCACGGACUGGAUCUGGGCCGGCCUCGACCCGGACACGGACUACGACGUGGCGCUAGUGCCUGAGUCCAACGUGCGCCUCCUGAGGCCCCAGAUCCUGCGGGUGCGCACGCGGCCCGGUGAGGCAGGGCCGGGGGCUUCGGGCCCGGAGUCGGGGGCUGGGCCGGCCCCCACGCAGCUCGCCGCCCUCCCCGCCCCAGAGGAGGCCGGGCCAGAGCGCAUCGUCAUCUCCCACGCCCGGCCGCGCAGCCUCCGCGUGAGUUGGGCCCCAGCGCUGGGCUCAGCCGCGGCGCUCGGCUACCACGUGCAGUUCGGGCCGCUGCGGGGCGGGGAGGCGCAGCGGGUGGAGGUGCCCGCGGGCCGCAACUGCACCACGCUGCAGGGCCUGGCGCCGGGCACCGCCUACCUGGUGACCGUGACCGCCGCCUUCCGCUCGGGCCGCGAGAGCGCGCUGUCCGCCAAGGCCUGCACGCCCGACGGCCCGCGCCCGCGCCCACGCCCCGUGCCCCGCGCCCCGACCCCGGGGACCGCCAGCCGUGAGCCGUAAGCCGGCGUCCCCGCCCAGCCGAGAGGGCCGGCGCCUACCUGAGGGCCCCUGUGUCCCGAACCCGGAGCGGAGGCGCCCAACCCGGCAGACGGGUGCAGGCCCGGCCUUUCCCCACGCGGACUCCGCGCGACCCCGGCCCUCUCCCUGCGGCCGCAGGGCUUCCCCGCCUGGCGCCUGCCCUCCAGGGCUGGGGCCUCGCCUGGCGGGACCCCGCAGCAGCCCCGGCCCCAUCCCCGCCCAGAGCCGGGCGUCGUGUGGGUCCGUGGGUGAUAAUUGAGAGCGUCAGACCCAGGACUGUUCAGGGAGGAGCCCCGGUCAGACUCCCACGUGUGAAGACCGGGCCCCAAGUGGCAAGGGCUGGCCUGGGGCGGGCAGCUUGGGUCCUGGACGUUGAUAGGAAGCGGAAGGGGAAUCGCGGGAAGCUGGCCCAGGUCAGGUCCGCAAAGGCUUCUGAAGAAGAGGAAGGGCGAGUAGGGGCACCUGGACGCUGAUGGUGGCCAGGAUGCUCAGCUGGCCAGGAGGGCAGCACCUGCUGGGGACGGUGGCCCUGCCUUCAUGCCCAGGACACCAGCUGGGUCCAGCUAGCAGCCACUGGGAAUCAGAGGAAUGGGGCAGAGCUGGGCAUUCAGGACCUUGAGGACACGUGACCCCACCCGCCCACCGCCACUAUCAGGCCCCGGGACCGCACUGACAGGAAACCUUCCGUCGUGAGGGAGCACUUCCCAGGGGCCGCAGGGACGACACUCUCCAGGGAGGCCCCAGCAACCACACCAUCUUCUUGCUGUGAGAGGUCUCACCCCGGGCUACCUCCUGUCACUACUCACUGCCCUGGGGUCCGUGGGCAAGUUGCCCAGGGUGGGGGUGCCUAGCCAGGUGCAGUCCCCGCCCCGCCUAGUCCUCGGCGUCACGCAAUGCUCACCUCGCCUCUUCCCCACUAACAUCCCAGACUUUAAAAUUCAGUAAAUCAGAUGUACACCGAGCCUGCAGUCUCGCUAGGAUGCUUUACUCCUCCACAAACAGCAGCCGCCGACAGGACAGCUUGUGAACGUCUCCGCCUUUUGGGGUGUCCGGGGAGAGGAGGUGGAGCUGUCCCCUCCCAGUGUCAGGCCUCCUUGGUCCUCAUGUGCACCUUUUAUUCAGAGAGCUUGGGCCCCCUUCCUUUGGAGCUGGGCCCAGGGCAGGUGGCUGGAAUGCAGAGGACAAGGGGGCUGGGGCCUCUGCAGGGCCAUUCCCACCGCAGUCUCUGCCACGGCCCGGAGCCCUGGGCCCAGGGCCACGCGGGCUCCCUCUGCUGGCAAAGCCACACCCUGCACCGCAUGGGGUCCACUGCCCCUUUCCCCACGUGGACUCUGCGUGACCCCAGGAACUGCAGCAUUGAGGUGGUCUCAGUCCCUCCCUCAGGUCUGGUGGGCAUUGUGCCAGGGGCCACCUUCGGGACAGCUGGCCUUGGCACCGUCUCCCAAGAACCCAGCUCUGUGCAUCCCGUGGCCCCACCAGAAACCCAAGGCCACACCGCCCACCAGCUGGGUGUGGUCACCAUUCAUGGAGGGCCGGCUGGGGCCAGGCUCACCACGCAGAGUUUGCCCUCCGGUGUGAUGAUGCAUGAGACACAGUAGGCCCCCCUGCCUGUGUGUGCAGGGGGUGUCUGUGGGGGGGCCCUGCUGGCUGGACUUUGGGUUUCUCCUGAGCUCCCCUUAGCCCCCAAGUCAGGCCACGGAGGCCUGAGUAGGACCCAUGGGCUGUGUGUGUCACUGCAGGUGGCGUGCUCACAACUGCACUGCUGGUCGGCAGGUGGCCAGGGUUGCAGGCCCGGGCCUCGGGCCCCACCUCCUCUGGAGGGGUAGGAUCUCCUUCGUGCAGCCCCUGCCCCCUACCCUGUUCUCCGGAGUGUUGGCAGAUCUGAGCCCACGGUCACGUGAGAGGAGAUGCCUCUUGCACACUGAGCCCAGGCCCAGCUCACGGAGCACCCUGCAGGUGGCAGCGGGGCACCAGGGGCUCAUUCCUGGUGGCCUCAGUGGCUUCUGUGGACGACUCAGACUCACAUGAGAAGCUGGGAGGAGCUCCAGCUCUGCAAUCCCGAGAGGGCAGAGCGGGGGCCCUGGCCACAACCCUGCUCCCCACAUACCCGUCUGGCAGAGGCUCUGCCUCCCCUCUGCCCAUCUCUGCACACCAAGGCUGAGCACAGCACAAGGCCUCACGGAGAGGGUGAAAAGGCACUGCCGUCUCCAUCUCAGUGCCAAGGAAUGCCCCUUUCAGAAGCCCUCGUCUGAGAAGUGCUGCCCCUUAUGUAGCCCCAGGCAUUUUAAAAUCUUUGAAUCUGCACCAAGUCUCAGAACAGCUCUGGCCCCGGAGUGCUCCGUCCAGGCCGCUGUGAACCGGCUGUCCCCGCGUCUCCUCCACCUCCCCUGACACAAUCCUGGCCCCGACUCAGUCCACCCAGGGUGCAGUGCAGAGGCUGAUACCCGCCAGGACUUCCUUGCCAAGGGCCCGGCCACGUCACAAGGCCACUGCACGCUUUUCGACAUGCACCUGGAAAUCGGGAAGGGCCAUGCUGCAGUUGCUUCUAGUUGAGACGAGAAGAGCGACAAGGUUGUGAUCCACGUGGCAGGUGUUCAGAAGGCUGGGGGCGGGCAGCGCUGGGGAGAGCCCUGGGUACUUCGAGGAGACCCCGAAGGGAGGCUGCUCCCACACCUGCGCCAGUUUCCACCCUCUCUGUGAGCAGGGCUGCGGUCACCUCCCACAUCUGAAGAGAACCAACCUGAGGAUUUCACGCUGGCUGCGUGCCAGACCAGUCCCUGACAGGUUGUGCGAGGCCCUUCGCUGGACAGCCCAUUGCUGGCCACUGGACGGAGAGGCAGAGGGGGCUGAAAUUCGGGCCCAUGCCUCUGUGAGCGAUGACGGAGCAACAGCUCUCCAGCACGUGAAGCUCUCCAGACAGCUGUUCGUGAGAAGCCAGACAGAGGCCUGGGGUCUCAGUCCAGAUUUCUGGGGAGUGGGGUGUCCAAGCGUGGGCCACGCUGCUGGGAGCCACCUAGGGAAGCAGGUCGCCUGUUUCUAUAGUGACGGUAAUAAACCAAGUCAAUUUUCUAUAGUGA